UGAUCUGCCUCUGUGUCUCCAGUGCCUGGCUCAGGGCCUGGCACACAUCGGGUGGAGGAGAUGUUCAUUGAAUGACCAUGACUUUGUUACUUAACCCAGCCAGAGCAGGAGGAGUCAGGACAGCUGCCAGGAAGAAGGAAGAAGGAGGCUUUGAGCUCAGUUUUGGAAGAGAAGUUAGCCAGGCUAACAAAGCAAGAAGGGCCAGGCGUUCCAGGCAGAAAAAUCUAGAAAGGUCAAGUCACCAGUGUUCAGGGAGGUAAAGUGACUUCUGCAAGCAGGAGGAAAUUUUGGAUGGCUGGAUACGAGAGACACGGAAGACGGUGGCUGGAAGAAACGCUAAUGGACUCCACUACAGCGACUGCUGAGCUGGGCUGGAUGGUGCAUCCUCCAUCAGGGUGGGAAGAGGUGAGUGGCUACGAUGAGAACAUGAACACGAUCCGCACGUACCAGGUGUGCAACGUGUUUGAGUCAAGCCAGAACAACUGGCUACGGACCAAGUUUAUCCGGCGCCGUGGCGCCCACCGCAUCCACGUGGAGAUGAAGUUUUCGGUGCGUGACUGCAGCAGCAUCCCCAGCGUGCCUGGCUCCUGCAAGGAGACCUUCAACCUCUAUUACUAUGAGGCUGACUUUGACUCGGCCACCAAGACCUUCCCCAACUGGAUGGAGAAUCCAUGGGUGAAGGUGGAUACCAUUGCAGCCGACGAGAGCUUCUCCCAGGUGGACCUGGGUGGCCGCGUCAUGAAAAUCAACACCGAGGUGCGGAGCUUCGGACCUGUGUCCCGCAGCGGCUUCUACCUGGCCUUCCAGGACUAUGGCGGCUGCAUGUCCCUCAUCGCCGUGCGUGUCUUCUACCGCAAGUGCCCCCGCAUCAUCCAGAAUGGCGCCAUCUUCCAGGAAACCCUGUCGGGGGCUGAGAGCACAUCGCUGGUGGCUGCCCGGGGCAGCUGCAUCGCCAAUGCGGAAGAGGUGGAUGUACCCAUCAAGCUCUACUGUAACGGGGACGGCGAGUGGCUGGUGCCCAUCGGGCGCUGCAUGUGCAAAGCAGGCUUCGAGGCCGUUGAGAAUGGCACCGUCUGCCGAGGUUGUCCAUCUGGGACUUUCAAGGCCAACCAAGGGGAUGAGGCCUGUACCCACUGUCCCAUCAACAGCCGGACCACUUCUGAAGGGGCCACCAACUGUGUCUGCCGCAAUGGCUACUACAGAGCAGACCUGGACCCCCUGGACAUGCCCUGCACAACCAUCCCCUCCGCGCCCCAGGCUGUGAUUUCCAGUGUCAAUGAGACCUCCCUCAUGCUGGAGUGGACCCCUCCCCGCGACUCCGGAGGCCGAGAGGACCUCGUCUACAACAUCAUCUGCAAGAGCUGUGGCUCGGGCCGGGGUGCCUGCACCCGCUGCGGGGACAAUGUACAGUACGCACCACGCCAGCUAGGCCUGACCGAGCCACGCAUUUACAUCAGUGACCUGCUGGCCCACACCCAGUACACCUUCGAGAUCCAGGCUGUGAACGGCGUUACUGACCAGAGCCCCUUCUCGCCUCAGUUCGCCUCUGUGAACAUCACCACCAACCAGGCAGCUCCAUCGGCAGUGUCCAUCAUGCAUCAGGUGAGCCGCACCGUGGACAGCAUUACCCUGUCGUGGUCCCAGCCGGACCAGCCCAAUGGCGUGAUCCUGGACUAUGAGCUGCAGUACUAUGAGAAGGAGCUCAGUGAGUACAACGCCACAGCCAUAAAAAGCCCCACCAACACGGUCACCGUGCAGGGCCUCAAAGCCGGCGCCAUCUAUGUCUUCCAGGUGCGGGCACGCACCGUGGCAGGUUACGGGCGCUACAGCGGCAAGAUGUACUUCCAGACCAUGACAGAAGCCGAGUACCAGACAAGCAUCCAGGAGAAGUUGCCACUCAUCAUCGGCUCCUCGGCCGCUGGCCUGGUCUUCCUCAUUGCUGUGGUUGUCAUCGCCAUCGUGUGUAACAGAAGACGGGGGUUUGAGCGUGCUGACUCGGAGUACACGGACAAGCUGCAACACUACACCAGUGGCCACAUGACCCCAGGCAUGAAGAUCUACAUCGAUCCUUUCACCUACGAGGACCCCAACGAGGCAGUGCGGGAGUUUGCCAAGGAAAUUGACAUCUCCUGUGUCAAAAUUGAGCAGGUGAUCGGAGCAGGGGAGUUUGGCGAGGUCUGCAGUGGCCACCUGAAGCUGCCAGGCAAGAGAGAGAUCUUUGUGGCCAUCAAGACGCUCAAGUCGGGCUACACGGAGAAGCAGCGCCGGGACUUCCUGAGCGAAGCCUCCAUCAUGGGCCAGUUCGACCAUCCCAACGUCAUCCACCUGGAGGGUGUCGUGACCAAGAGCACACCUGUGAUGAUCAUCACCGAGUUCAUGGAGAAUGGCUCCCUGGACUCCUUUCUCCGGCAAAACGAUGGGCAGUUCACAGUCAUCCAGCUGGUGGGCAUGCUUCGGGGCAUCGCAGCUGGCAUGAAGUACCUGGCAGACAUGAACUAUGUUCACCGUGACCUGGCUGCCCGCAACAUCCUCGUCAACAGCAACCUGGUCUGCAAGGUGUCGGACUUUGGGCUCUCACGCUUUCUAGAGGACGAUACCUCAGACCCCACCUACACCAGUGCCCUGGGCGGAAAGAUCCCCAUCCGCUGGACAGCCCCGGAAGCCAUCCAGUACCGGAAGUUCACCUCGGCCAGUGAUGUGUGGAGCUACGGCAUUGUCAUGUGGGAGGUGAUGUCCUAUGGGGAGCGGCCCUACUGGGACAUGACCAACCAGGAUGUAAUCAAUGCCAUUGAGCAGGACUAUCGGCUGCCACCGCCCAUGGACUGCCCGAGCGCCCUGCACCAACUCAUGCUGGACUGUUGGCAGAAGGACCGCAACCACCGGCCCAAGUUCGGCCAAAUUGUCAACACGCUAGACAAGAUGAUCCGCAAUCCCAACAGCCUCAAAGCCAUGGCGCCCCUCUCCUCUGGCAUCAACCUGCCGCUGCUGGACCGCACGAUCCCCGACUACACCAGCUUUAACACGGUGGACGAGUGGCUGGAGGCCAUCAAGAUGGGGCAGUACAAGGAGAGCUUCGCCAAUGCCGGCUUCACCUCCUUUGACGUCGUGUCUCAGAUGAUGAUGGAGGACAUUCUCCGGGUUGGGGUCACUUUGGCUGGCCACCAGAAAAAAAUCCUGAACAGUAUCCAGGUGAUGCGGGCGCAGAUGAACCAGAUUCAGUCUGUGGAGGUUUGACAUUCACCUGCCUCGGCUCACCUCUUCCUCCAAGCCCCGCCCCCUCUGCCCCACGUGCCGGCCCUCCUGGUGCUCUAUCCACUGCAGGGCCAGCCACUCGCCAGGAGGCCACGGGCCACGGGAAGAACCAAGCGGUGCCAGCCACGAGACGUCACCAAGAAAACAUGCAACUCAAACGACGGAAAAAAAAAGGGAAUGGGAAAAAAGAAAACAGAUCCUGGGAGGGGGCGGGAAAUACAAGGAAUAUUUUUUAAAGAGGAUUCUCAUAAGGAAAGCAAUGACUGUUCUUGCGGGGGAUAAAAAAGGGCUUGGGAGAUUCAUGCGAUGUGUCCAAUCGGAGACAAAAGCAGUUUCUCUCCAACUCCCUCUGGGAAGGUGACCUGGCCAGAGCCAAGAAACACUUUCAGAAAAACAAAUGUGAAGGGGAGAGACAGGGGCCGCCCUUGGCUCCUGUCCCUGCUGCUCCUCUAGGCCUCACUCAACAACCAAGCGCCUGGAGGACGGGACAGAUGGACAGACAGCCACCCUGAGAACCCCUCUGGGAAAAUCUAUUCCUGCCACCACUGGGCAAACAGAAGAAUUUUUCUGUCUUUGGAGAGUAUUUUAGAAACUCCAAUGAAAGACACUGUUUCUCCUGUUGGCUCACAGGGCUGAAAGGGGCUUUUGUCCUCCUGGGUCAGGGAGAACGCGGGGACCCCAGAAAGGUCAGCCUUCCUGAGGAUGGGCAACCCCCAGGUCUGCAGCUCCAGGUACAUAUCACGCGCACAGCCUGGCAGCCUGGCCCUCCUGGUGCCCACUCCCGCCAGCCCCUGCCUCGAGGACUGAUACUGCAGUGACUGCCGUCAGCUCCGACUGCCGCUGAGAAGGGUUGAUCCUGCAUCUGGGUUUGUUUACAGCAAUUCCUGGACUCGGGGGUAUUUUGGUCACAGGGUGGUUUUGGUUUAGGGGGUUUGUUUGUUGGGUUGUUUUUUGUUUUUUGGUUUUUUUUAAUGACAAUGAAGUGACACUUUGACAUUUCCUACCUUUUGAGGACUUGAUCCUUCUCCAGGAAGAAGGUGCUUUCUGCUUACUGACUUAGGCAAUACACCAAGGGCGAGAUUUUAUAUGCACAUUUCUGGAUUUUUUUAUACGGUUUUCAUUGACACUCUUCCCUCCUCCCACCUGCCACCAGGCCUCACCAAAGCCCACUGCCAUGGGGCCAUCUGGGCCAUUCAGAGACUGGAGUGAGAUUUGGGUGUGGAGGGGGAGGCGCCAAGGUGGAGGAGCUUCCCACUCCAGGACUGUUGAUGAAAGGGACAGAUUGAGGAGGAAGUGGGCUCUGAGGCUGCAGGGCUGGAAGUCCUUGCCCACUUCCCACUCUCCUGCCCCAAUCUAUCUAGUACUUCCCAGGCAAAUAGGCCCCUUUGAGGCUCCUGAGUGCCCUCAGAUGGUCAAAACCCAGUUUUCCCUCUGGGAGCCUAAACCAGGCUGCAUCGGAGGCCAGGACCCGGAUCAUUCACUGUGAUACCCUGCCCUCCAGAGGGUGCGCUCAGAGACACGGGCAAGCAUGCCUCUUCCCUUCCCUGGAGAGAAAGUGUGUGAUUUCUCUCCCACCUCCUUCCCCCCACCAGACCUUUGCUGGGCCUAAAGGUCUUGGCCAUGGGGACGCCCUCAGUCUAGGGAUCUGGCCACAGACUCCCUCCUGUGAACCAACACAGACACCCAAGCAGAGCAAUCAGUUAGUGAAUUGAAUGGAAAUAAACGCUUUAGUUAUAAUAUGACCCCUGUUCUCUGUAAGUUCCAAGGGAGACCUUGGUACCCUUGGGAUGCACGUGACCCAGGUGCUAAGGGUUGCUCUUCUAAGCAGCCCUUCCUCCCUCAGGCUUCCAGAAAGCCCAGGGCAGAGAAAACACAUGGAGAACGACAGCUCCACGUGGCCUUUCUGGCCCUGGCUUGUCAAAAGCACAGGCAACAAAGGAAGUGAGUUGGAAGUGGCUCAGAACUCAGCCUUCGAUGCCCUGGGAAUCAGGGUGAGCCCCUGCAGGUACAUAAGUAGCAGAGAAUUGACGAGAGUGCACUCGGAAGAGGGUCUGAGUGUCAGGUGAGCUGUCAUAGUGGGAACGUGAGGGUCUUAGAGUGCUCAUGUACCCCCAGGCACAGCCAACUCUGGUUUUCUCUGUGCAAAUGAGCUCUUGCUCACAUUAAAAUCAGAAUUGUCCACGUGGCAGGAGGAGGCAGGGAGAUGGAUGUGCCAUGGAUAUCGGGUCUGGCUGAGGAAGGGGAGCCAAGGAGACUACCUCUCGGGACCUUUCCCAGAUCCGAGGAGAUGGCCAGUGAGAAAGAUUCGGGCCACAGGCAGCCAGCUAGAAGCGCCACGGUCAGAGUGAACAUCCAGCACAGCACAGCCCAUCGUCUGUCACUCACCUGUUCCGGGAGCCUGAGCUGCAAAGGGAAGGAAGGGAUUAGAGAGAAGUGUGGGCCCCCCAUGGGGACAGCAGGGCAAGCCACAGGGAAAGCAUUGGCAGGUUUCCCACAAACUGGCCGGCAGUGGCCCACUGGCCUUCACUUUGUGCCCCAAAGGUGCCCUGCGCGGGUGGCAGCUGUCUCGGCACACAAGGUCACCUUCUGGUGGGAGCUGCCCUGAUGCUCUUUAGAUUAGUUCUGUCUCCCCAGCCCACCCCCCAACUGUUCUGGGGCCCCACAUGGGGCUGGCAGUCGGUGCUUCCCGUCAGAUGGCUUCCUGUCCUAAGCCGCUGAGCUGGUGACCACUAGCCAGCAUGUCUGCCCCUCCACCCUCCAGGGCCGAGGUCCUCAGUGGCCAUGGCCCCCUGCAAACCUGCUUCCCAGAGCACAGGUGCUACCAGACCUCUGUGUCUCCACUUCAGGGUAACAAACAGAUGUCACUGUGACUGUCCCAGGGGUACAGGCGCUGCUCACAUCUCUUCCACCCCCACCCACCCACCCCACCCGCUACCGGGGCAGUCGCCCCGCCCCAACCUCUUGCUUGCUGCUCAGCGGGGAGUGGCAGGCCAUGUUGCCAAGCGCCUUCCACUUACACCACCCGCUCACCCAGGCACACAGCUCUGAGCCACCCGCUGCCUGGUUACUAAUCCUUUCCUGGCUCAACCUCCCCAAGUGCCAGCCCCCGCCUGCCCAGCAGUGUUAGGGGAGUUUCCGGCUGCUCUGCACACAGUUGGUACUGCAGGAAAGAAAGCUGCCUUGUAAACACAGGCCAGGGCACCGUGGAAAUGGGGACCAGCUGCUCUGGGAGGGUGCAGCUAGCAGAGCUGUGCAGCGCCAGGCUGGGUAGGAGAGAGCCAUGCUACCCACCCGCACCCCUACUGCUACGAAGCCCCCAGAAUGGGUCAUUGUUGGUGCUCAGCAGUCCUCUCCCUCGGGGAUGAUAUCCAAAAUAUCAACUGCGAAGACUCGGGCAGACCAAUCAGAAUAGAUGAUGGCCUGAGUGCUGGACCAGAGGCCUCAGAGCAGGGACCCGGGUGGCGGGGCAGUAGGAGACACUUAAGGGACUCAGGGCUAUGGCUGUUUACUAACCAGCAGUGCCUCUUACUCAGAUGGCAUCAGCUGAACUUUCCCCAUCAUUUCUAGUUGGUCCCCACCCUGCCACCAUCUAGGGGCUUCUCUGCCACCACCUUGUGAGCAGUUGCUAGCCUCACACUCCUCUCCCAUCAGGGGCUCAUCUCCAAAAGGCUGGGAGCUCCCGCCCUGCCCAGUUAAUCCUCCUGCCUCACUGAAGCACAGGAAGGACCCAGGCCCCAGACCAUCACCCACCCCAGGGCUGGGCCCUGGGCCACUCCUGGCUCACUCCAGGGCCCCUGUUGUUUGAAGAUGGUACCAAAGGCUGGAAGACUCUUGCUAGGGAAGAUAACGUAAAUGCAUUCAAAAGACAGGGUACCACAUGAUGCUAGGGAAAGUGCGUCAUGACCGCAGGGUAGCAGCCUGCUCCUGUCACUAGGGAUGUGAAUCUGGGGAGACACUUCCCCUCACUGAGCCAUCUGUAAAAUGAGAGCAUUGGACUGGGUGAGGCAGGCUGUGCAAAACACUUAUACACCUUAGUCCCAUGAGGAAGGAGUAUUCCCCCUGCAUAUUUUGGGGGGAAACUGAGGCUCAGGGGGAUGAAGUACUUUGCUCAGGGUAACACAGCCAGGAAGGAGCAGAGCAAGGCCAUGAGCUUUGGAUUUUUCUGUUUCCAAUGUCUCCUCUACCGUGCUCAAUUAGAUGAUGAGAAACAGUUGGUGUCUGAUGCUGGCCAAUAAGAGAAAAGAAAGCUCAAGUGGGCUGGGGCUGUCAGGGAGGGCUUCAUGGAGAGGCUGUCUUGAAAAUGACAGAGGUCAAAAGAAAGGUCACUCCAAGACGCAGCUGCCAGAAUGGUCCAACACAGUGAGGAGUUGUGUCUGGAUGGGCCAGUGGAACGGGGGAAGUGAAGGUUGAUAUAAGUGGAGGUUGAGGCAGUUUAGGCGUGAUGUACAGUCCAGCCACAGCAGGUUCUUGAGCAGGAGGGUAGCAUAGUGAGCAUCAGGUUCUAGGAAGAAGCACCAGUUCAGCCAUCAGAUGGGGCAGGAUGCCUCCCAGCUACUCCUCUCCCCGAGAAGGAAUUGCCCCCGGAGCGGCCCUCAUUUAUUCCAGGAGAAGCCAGGCCCUGCUGCUUCAGUUUCCAUCCUCACUGACGCAGAUAAUCCAAAGAGUCACUUCAGCUGCUUGGAACAGCAGGGUUGGGUCUUGUGCUACCUGAUUCUUAAUUUGGCUGAUGUCUACCCCAUUUCCUCCAGGCUUCUCUAGAGGUGGCAGGGGUGGGGUGGGGAGAAAGCUGCCAGACACCAAAGGAGCUGAGCCUGGCGGGGGCGGGCGUGCGGGUGGGCAUGAGAAAUUGCUCAGGAAACCCAUCCCUGCCCUGGUCACCCUAGUCCUGGAGAGAUCACCCAGACAUGUUGGAAUGAGUCUGGGGUCCUGUCUUUUCCAAUAAUGUGUUAUCCUGGGGAAACCCAGAGGGAAGUUGAGGGAGCCCCACUGUGCUGUGUGAUGCUACAUACGCAUGCGAAUACACCACCGGGUGGCCUUGACCCAGCCUUCUGCAAAAUGGCUUCUGCCAUCAAACUUAAGGUGGAGAAUGGUCUUGCAGCUGCCAGUUUUUCCUUCAGAGAAACUAAGGUCAGAGUGUUGGCUGCAGAAAAGGACUUGGCCUUUGUCACAUAACAGGAAAGAGAGUCAACUCCGGGCACACCCCCUCGGAGGCUAAUCUCAGGAGGUUGGAACCACAGGGAUUGCAAUAAUCGCUGAAUACUUACCAUAUGCCAGGUGCCAAAGCAUUAUCCUCUCCACUUUAUGAGUGAGGAAACUGAUUCCCAGAGGUGAUUCCCAGAAGAUUCCAACCAGGCCAUCUGUCUGUAGUCCUUCCUUCCCACCUCCUGGGAUUUCUCAAAAUGUUUGCCAUCGCCCACCUGUAUCAGAAUCUCCUGGGCUAUUUAUUGUUUAACUUGCAGACUCCUGGGCGCCACCCCAACCCCCUAAAUCAGAAUCCCUGGGGUUGGGCCCAAGAGUCUCCAUUUUUUGACAAGCUCCUCCAGGAGAUUCCUCCAGACAUGGAAAUCCUCACUUGACUCUUCCCCCAUAACAAACUGCCCUGAUGUCUGCAGAGAGAGGGUCUGCUGUAGACAGGGAUUAAGAAAAAGCAGGACAUUUUCAGAUAGGAUGCCCAAACCCAGACGCAGAUUAGGACCCAUGAAGUAGGGGGUAGAGCUGACCCUCAGGAAUGUGCCCAGACAGAGCUAAGCUUUCAGGAAAAUUAGAAAGACCCUCAGACCCAGAGUCUGUCUGAGUUUAGCUUCGCAGCAUGAAGGCUGCCUUGAGAAAGCUGAUAUAACAAGAAGCAGCAGAAAUUUAAUACUUUGGAGGGGCCCAGCAACCCACUCAGGGCCACCCUGGGAGACCCCACAGACCCCAAGGCUAUGGUCCAGACCUGUUCACUCAACACCUGGCCAGGCGGGGCCUCCAGCUGGACCUAGAGCUACAGAUGCCCCACCACCACUACCAAGCCCGGCUACCCAGACCAAGACACGGCUUUUCCUGGAGGAGAGAGAGAGCAAAGGCCCUGUCUCUACCCAAGACCUAACGGCCCCUGUUGAAGGAGAGGGAGCAGGAGAGGGAGGAGGGAGGAGGUCACAGCCAGGACCACAUACACUCUUGGGGGCCCUGCUGAGACUGCAAGAGUCAUGAAUUCUAACGUUCCACAGGUGAAAGAUUCCAAGAUUCUAGGAUUGCAAAACCCCAUCAUUCUAAGAUUCCAAUGGAAUGAUUCCAUGUUUCUAAGAUUCCAUCACACUAUGAUUCUAUGCUGCUAAUUCUUGAAAUUUCGAGUCUCAUUGUUCGUUGCUGUUCCCCAGACCUGUGGGCCCUAGCAUUUUUUUAAAAGCACAAAAAAAAAAGAGCAAGAAAGAGAGAAAGAGAUGGGGAGGGAGACAGCUGAAAACAGAUACUAAGAAAAGCUCCAUCCCUUGGAUCUGAGUUACAGAUGCACCUUGGCAAGGGCCAAAGACCCUCCUUUUGAGUGGGGUGCAGAACGUCUUUCCCUGGUAGAGUGGCAGAAUUGCAUGCAUCAGGCCUUCCUGGGGGUAAAAGGGGCUGGCUGUUCCAGGCUACAGCUGAGUAAAGCCCCACACAGGCCACAGUGCCCACUGGCUGGUGGACCUAGGAACCAAGCAGGGCCCCACUGGCUCAGUCUGGGGAGGGACUCAUCUGGGGUGGAAUUUCCCUCCCUGCAGCAAGGAAGCUGCAGGGCCAGGAAUUUGCCUUGGGAGACCCCCACUGAGGAAUAUUUCCGAAGCAGAACCCCUUCCUAUUCAGAGCCAGAGUCUUAACACUGGACAACCACAGGGUGUUGCUGCAAACUCCAGAGCCAGGUGCCUUCCCUCUGACAUUUGGGACAUAGCUUCCAUGGCCACACAGCCUUCGCCCCCUUCCAAGACCCCCCUUGACCUUUCUAAUCUUAGUCACUGCCUUCCAGAGCUGGGAGGCCACACGGCAGAGGUGCCUGUGAAUCACUCCGUCAUCAGCCUGGCCGCUUUCCCCUCUGUGGAGAGGGACUCUGAUGGGCAGGGGGCACCAAGUUGAGCCUCUGAGGCUGGCCCAGCAUAGGCCAGGCAGGGACAUUCACUCACAACCAGCCUUUUUGGACUCUAGAGAAGAGUAAUUACCACUUGGUCAUGCCCAGCCCCCAAAUCAUAAUCAUAGCUGCUAUUUCUUGAGUGCCAGCAAUGUGCCAGGCACCGUGCCCAACUUUUUAUACACAAUGUCUUGCCUAAUCCUCACACCUCUGUGAGACAGGUACAAUUAUUACUCCCAUUCCACAGACUAGCAAACUCAGAGACGUGACAUGGUGGCUCUCCCAGGUCACACAGCCAGUAAGUGGCCUCUGACCCCAGUACCCCCCACUUAAUCACCAUGCUAUGCUGCUACCAGUGGUACACACUCAGCCCCUCUCCACUGUCAGAUCCUUUGCCAGUCAAAUCCCAGAUCCCCGGGGGGGCACUGUGGCACCCUCUUUGAGCGUGGCCUCCCUGGAGCUGCUGUCAGAGCCAUGGGCUGUGGGAGUGAGUGUGCACACUCCUUCUCCUGAAGUGUCUGCCCCAGCCUGAGCUAUGCAGACCGGAGCUCUCAACCAGGGUAUGGGGCUGUCUGGCAGGGUUUCCCAGAACCCUGUUUCCUGUGGUCAUAAAUAUGGGUUUUCCUGACAAUGUUGGGAGGUCAGGGACUGAUACAGCUGGGGUUCCAACCGCCGUGGGUCAGACCUGGCUCCUCCGGACCCCACUGCUGUGACCAAGGAAAUCUCACCAGCUGUGUCCAAGAUCAACCCUGACCCUGUUACUCCAAUGCCUUUGUAGGAGUAUUUUUAGCAGAACCGUUUUUUUCCCAAAAUAAAUGUGAAUUGUAAAAAUUA